GAGAUGUAGUGUGCACUUUUCGGCCCCCGUCGCGGGAGCCGCUUCGGGCCUUCUGGGCAUGUCUGCCAUAUGGCUCCAGGUUUGUUUUUCUCCCCGGCACUCUGACGGGGAGGGCUCCCGGCAUCUCCUGGCGUCCGGGUAGAGGACGCGGAGGGUCGCAGCUUCAUUGCCUGAUGUCUUCGGGAAGUAUUUUGAAGUCAUCGUGGCUGUGGAUUGGGGAAUUUCUUGUUUCCACUGACCUGUGAGGCCGCGCACGCGGAGGGAGGCACCCCAGGCCCUCCGGCACUGUCCAGCCUCGCCUGUGUCCCCAUUAGCACCAGUGGGCAUUUUCAGAGGGUCCAGCUCAUGGCUCAAGUGACAGGAAGAUGUAGGAGCUUUCUGUCUUGAAUGAGGAUUCGAACCAAAGGGCUUAGGCCCAGCUGUCUUGGAGCAAAGCAGCUGUUGUGGGACCCCCACAGGCUGGGAGCUUUGUGCCCAUUCAGAUGUGGGGGCAGAAGAGGGCAAGGCCGAAGGAGCAGACAGCACCGCUUCUUGGGGAGUUGUGAAGGCAUCAUGCGGAGGGAAGAGCUUAGCAGCCAAGUGGAGGACAGCACCCUCCAUGCCUGGAUUCGUUACUCGCUCGUUCUAGAUGCUGAGCUGCUGGCGCACUGCAGCACAACUAGAGAUGUACGGAUGCCCCCAUCUUGAUCUUACAGAAUCAGAGGUACAGCCGCGAGAAAGGUCUAGUCAAGAACAGACAGAGUCGCUUGAGGACUCAGGAGGGUGUUUGCUGCGUUGACAACAGACUACACCCUCACAGUUUGCUCUGCUCUUCCAACACCAGUGGAAGAUGAUCACAUCCCAGGGAUCAGUGUCGUUUAGGGAUGUGACUGUGGGCUUCACUCAAGAGGAGUGGCAGCAUCUGGACCCUGCUCAGAGGACCCUGUACAGGGAUGUGAUGCUGGAGAACUACAGCCACCUUGUCUCAGUAGGGUAUUGCAUUCCUAAACCAGAAGUGAUUCUCAAGUUGGAGAAAGGCGAGGAGCCAUGGAUAUUAGAGGAAAAAUUUCCAAGCCAGAGUCAUCUGGGUGAGUUAGUAUGUGCCAGAUGGAAUUUAAAGGAAGGUAGAUCACAAAGGAAUUAAUUAAUACCAGUAGAAACUAUUCAAUAAUGAAGUUCAAUGAGUUUAACAAAGGUGGAAAAUGUUUCUGUGAUGAAAAGCAUGAAAUAAUUCAUUCUGAAGAGGAACCUUCUGAAUAUAAUAAAAAUGGGAACAGCUUCUGGCUGAAUGAAGACCUCAUUUGGCAUCAGAAAAUUAAAAAUUGGGAACAAUCUUUUGAAUACAAUGAAUGUGGGAAAGCUUUCCCUGAGAAUUCACUCUUCCUUGUACAUAAGAGAGGUUACACAGGACAGAAAACCUGCAAAUAUACUGAACAUGGGAAAACCUGUGAUAUGUCAUUUUUCAUCACUCAUCAGCAAACACAUCCAAGAGAAAACCACUAUGGUAAUGAAUGUGGAGAAAAUAUCUUUGAGGAAUCCAUUCUCCUUGAACAUCAGAGUGUUUACCCAUUCAGCCAGAAGUUAAAUCUCACUCCAAUUCAGAGAACCCACUCAAUUAACAAUAUUAUUGAAUAUAAUGAGUGUGGAACAUUUUUCAGUGAAAAAUUAGUCCUUCAUUUACAACAGAGAACACAUACAGGAGAAAAACCUUAUGAAUGUCAUGAAUGUGGAAAAACCUUCACCCAGAAGUCAGCCCACACAAGACAUCAGAGAACACACACAGGGGGAAAACCCUAUGAAUGUCAUGAAUGUGGGAAGACCUUCUAUAAGAAUUCAGACCUCAUUAAACAUCAAAGAAUUCAUACAGGGGAGAGACCUUAUGGAUGUCAUGAAUGUGGGAAAUCCUUCAGUGAAAAGUCAACCCUUACUCAACAUCAAAGAACGCACACAGGGGAGAAACCAUAUGAAUGUCAUGAAUGUGGGAAAACCUUCUCAUUUAAGUCAGUCCUUACUGUGCAUCAGAAAACACACACAGGGGAGAAGCCCUAUGAAUGCUAUGCAUGUGGGAAAGCCUUUCUCAGAAAAUCAGACCUCAUUAAACAUCAAAGAAUACACACAGGUGAAAAACCUUAUGAAUGUAAUGAAUGUGGGAAGUCAUUCUCUGAGAAGUCAACCCUUACUAAACAUCUAAGAACUCACACAGGUGAGAAACCUUAUGAAUGUAUUCAGUGUGGAAAAUUUUUCUGCUACUACUCCGGUUUCACAGAACAUCUGAGAAGACACACAGGGGAGAAACCUUUUGGAUGUAAUGAAUGUGGGAAAACCUUCCGUCAGAAGUCAGCCCUAAUUGUUCACCAGAGAACUCAUAUAAGACAGAAACCCUAUGGAUGUAAUCAAUGUGGAAAAUCAUUCUGUGUGAAGUCAAAACUCAUUGCACAUCAUAGAACACACACAGGGGAGAAACCCUAUGAAUGUAAUGUUUGUGGAAAAUCAUUCUAUGUUAAGUCAAAACUAACUGUACAUCAGAGAAUACACUUGGGGAGAAACCCUAUAAAUGUAGUAAACGAGGGAAAUUACUCUGGGUGAAGUCAGAACUUUGUAGAACACAGAACAUAAAGGGUGAGAGAAAUCUGUUAAUAUAAUGAUAAUGAGAACACCUUUGCCCUGAAGUCAGUUCUCACAGUAUAGAAGAGAACUUAAAGAGGGAAAAAACAAUAUGAAGAUAGGGAAUGCAGGAAAACAUUAUUCUGGAAUUUGGACCAUACACUAUGUUACAAAACUAAAAGUGGAAAAAACUUAUUGGUGAAUGAAUAUAGGAAACAUUUUGCCCAAUGCCACUCUUCAUUAAACAUCAGAGAAUUCACACGGGGUGAAACCUGGGUCAGCAUCCCUAGGUUGAGAAGGGAUGCAUUUUUCUGCUACUACUACAGUUUCACAGAAUACCUGAGAAGACACACUUGGAGAAACCUUUUGGGUGUAAUGAAUGUGGGAAAACCUUUCAUCAGAAGUCAGCUCUAAUUGUUCACCACAGAACUCAUAUAAGACAGAAACCCUAUGGGUGUAAUGAAUGUGGAAAAUCAUUCUGUGUGAAGUCAAGAGGCCAGAGAAAAUGCACAAACUGUAGGAAACUAUAGGAAAGCAUUUACUAUGAGGUUAUAUUUUAUGGAGUAUAUGUAAUAAGAAGUAGCUUCUCAGUGAACAUCAGAUAGUAGAGAAAGUAUUUUUAACUGUAUCCAAUGUGUGGAUGUUUUAAGUUAAAAUCUAAAUUUAAUAUAGAACAGAGGUGUUGAGUUGCAGGAUAUCUAGCAAUUUAAGAAAAUGUGGAAAAAAUAUUUUUAUUGAGAAAUAGCAUUUUACUUUGUUAAUAUCUAGUUUAGUUCAUUGUCAAGACUGCUAUUUUCUAAGAGACUUCUAAAGACGCCACUCAAGCCAAUGGCUAUAAGUAGUUCAAAGGUUUAUUGCUUAGCCAUAUGAAAAAUAAGGGAAGAUUUUUUAGCAAGGGGACCCACAAACAAGAGUGCUCUUGUAUGUCCAGAAGAAAGAGAAAGACCAUCAAUCAGGGGCCAUAGUACAGGAGCCCACCAGCAGGAUUUUUGAAUAAUCCUAGGGCAGACUAAAUUCAGACGACCCAUCUCAGAAUGGUGGAUCAAAGCAGCAAGUCAAUUUGCCUUGUAUGCAACUUAUGAGGAUUAGUAGAAGAGAGUGGGUCCAGAUUUCUGGUGGUUUCUGCCCUGCAGAUGUCUAACACAUAAGCCAGGACAUUCUGCUGUGAGUGACUUAUUGUACCCAACUCUAUUUCUCUCCAUACUGAAACAUGUCUUUCAUAGGUGAUACAACUUUUUAAAAUGUAUGUGUAGAUAUAACUUAAAUAUGGAGCUUUCAAAAAGCACAAAUAGGCUGGACAUGGUGGCUCAUGCCUGUAAUCCCAGUACUUUGGGAGGCUGAGGUGGGCAAAUCACCUGAGGUCAGGAGUUCCAGACCAGCCUGGCCAACAUGAUGAAACCCUGUCUCUACUAAAAAUACAAAAAUUAGCCGGGCAUGGUGGUGCACAUCGGUAGUCCUGGCUACUAGAGAGGUUGAGGUGGGAGGAUCACUUGAACCUGGGAGGUGGGGGUUUCAGUGAGCUGAGAUCAUGCCACUGCACUCCAGCCUGAGUGACAGAGAGAGAUUCAAAAAACAAAAAAAAAGCAAAAAUAUACUUUGCUAUUGGGUAAGGUAUAGUAGUUGGCAGCAGAAUGGACCCAUUGAGGAUAACUAUAAAAUUACAGAAAAUAUUUAAAUGCAACUUAUUGCUAUAGAAGCAAAGAGGACUAAAGGGCAAAAUUCUAGAGAGUGGUAAAUCUCAGAAAGCACAAGCAUAAAAUGCAGCUCUGGGGGCCCUUUCCACUUCUGGCUAUAGGGAAGAACCUGAAUACUGAACUUGAUUCAGGCAGAGGACCAUAACCUGGGGGUCAGGGGAAGGCAUGGGGGGGACCAGAAACCAGAAGAACAAUCAAGACUGCAAUGAAAAAAAUGGAUACAUUAGGAGCUUCAAACACAUAUAAUUUCUCAAGAAAUUUCCAGAUGUCUCAUGCUGCAUAGGGCAGGAGCCUGAAAAGCUAAUUUGAGAAGAUAAUAAGUAGGAUUUUUGUUUUGUUUUGCAUUUUGCAGUACAAAGGAGAAAUGAUUAGAACUUAGGAAGUGCCAGUGGGUUGGUGAACAUGCCAUCAGUAAAAGCCCUGGAAACAAGGUCAUACUAGAGAUUGGUUGUGCCUUGUCACAACUGCAAACAAUACCUGAGUGGAGUAUUCAAAAACUUGCUUAGAAAGAAAACUCUAGGAACAGAUGGCUUCACUGAAGUUAUUCCAAAUAUUUAAGAAAUAAUACCAGGCUUUUAUAAACUUUUCUAGAAGAAAAAAGAUGGAACUUUUCCAAUUCAGUUUUUGAGGCCAGUACAACCUUGAUAACAAAACCUAAAAAAAAAACAACAAAAAAACCCAUAAAGCUAUAGACCAAAGUCUCAUAGAUUUAGAUGCAAAAUCCUAAAAUUGAAAAAAACAUCUAGCCAUAUCCAUAAACUAUAUCAUCACCAAGAGAUGUUUAUUAGGGCAAUCAAAAGAUUUAUUAUUUUAAAAAAAUCAGUGUGGACUUCCAUUCCUCUUUCUUUUGAUUCCCCCCUUUGACUUUUCAUGUAUCUCUCCUGCCUUCCUUCCCCAGAGUGGAGGAGUUAGACUUGCCUCGUGGGAUGAGAGGAGUUGUGGCUUUGUGUCUGCUGGCACCAAGAGGGCUGAGGGUGAGGUGUGGAAGGGACAGGGGGAGGAGAUGGGCAGCAUUGUUGAGAGAUUGGUAACACUGAGCAAAUAAAUAUGUUGAGAAUGAUGACAGCAAGAUUUCUCCAUUAGAGAAGGUAUUUAUAAAAAUAGGAAUGAGGAGAGCUAGAAAACCUGGAGUGUGGCAUUAGAAUAGAACUCAUAUCUUUUAAAUAUAUAGGAACAAAUAAAUAAAUUGUUGUGUGUGCACAUAUGCAUAUAUUUUGUGUUCAUUCUACUGAGAGGACCUAAACACAAUGACACCUCAGUAACAGUAAGCACACCAACUGCCAAGUUAUUAGUUCCUAAAUACUAUCCACAAAAAAGGGGAACAGGGAUGAUUCCUAGUCAGAGAUUGGGAGAAAUACAAGAUGAGCCUGAAUCAUCUCAUGUACCUGACAGUAAGAAAAUACUCUGGCUGGUCUCAGUGGCUCAUGUCUGUAAUUCUAGCAUGUUAGAAGGUCAAGGUGGGUGGGUUGCUUGAGCUCAGGAGUUUGAGACCAGCCUGGGCAACAUGGCACAAUUGUCUCUACAAAAAAUACAAAAAUUAGCCAGGCAUGGUGGCAUGCACCUGUAGUCCGAGGUACUCAGGAGGCAGAGACGUGGGAGGAUCGCUUGAGCCUGGGAGAUUGAGGCUGCACUGAGCUGUGAUCGUGCCACUGUACUCUAGCCUGGAAGACAGAGUGAGACCCCAUCUCAGGAAAAAAGAAAAAAAAAAAGAUGUCAUUCAGCAGGUUAAUGGAUAAACUGUGGAACAUCCAGAAAACUUUAACAUUCUUCAAAGAAAUAGAAAACACAAUCCUAAAAUUUAUAUGGGAACCACAAAAGACUUAGAAUAGUCAGCUAUCCUGAGCAAAAGGAAUCAAACUGGAGGAAUCAUAUUACCUGACUUCCAAUUAUUCAACAGAGCUACAGUAACCAAAACAGCAUGAUACUGGCAUAACAACAGACACAUAGGAACAGUAUAGACAACCCAGAAACAAAUUCAUACAUCUAUGGUGACCACUUUUGACAAAGGAAUGAAGAACAUACACUGGGGAAAAGAUAAUGUCUUUAAUAAAUGGUGCUGGGAAAACUGGAUAUCCAUAUGCAGAAGAAUGAAACUAGACCCCCAUCUCUUAGCAUAUACAAAAAUCAAAAUUAAUUAAAAAGUUAAAUCUAAGACCUCAAACUAUGAAACAGCUAAAAGAAAACAUCGGGGAAUCUCUCCAGGACAUUGGAGUGGGCAAAGAUUUCUUGUGUAAUACCUGACAAACAGGCAACCAAAGCAAAAGUGGACAAAUGGGAUCACAUCAAGUUAAAAAUCUUCUGCAUUGCAAAGGAAAUAACAAAGUGAAGAGACAACCCAUAGAAUGUGAGAUAAUAUUUGCAAACUAUCCAUCUGUAUUAGGCCAUUUUUGAAGUACUACAAAGAAAUACUUGAGACUGAGUAAUUUAUAAAGAAGAGGUUUAAUUGGCUCACGGUUUUGCAGGCUGUACAGGAAGCAUGGUGCUAACAUCUGAUCAGCUUGUAGGGAGGCAUCAGGAAGUUUCCAACCAUGGUGGAAGGCAAAAGGGGAAUAAGUAUCUCACAUGGCAGGUGCAGGGCAAAGAGAGGGGGGAAGGGAAGUGCCACACAACCAGAUCUUGUGAGUACUCAGAUUUUGUGAGGGGUGCUUGAGGUCAUGGAUACCCAUUUACCCUGAUGUGUUUAUACACAUUUCAUACCUGUAUUAAAAUAUCUCAUGUACCCCAUAAACAUAUACACCUACUUUGUACCCACAAAAAUUUAAAAAUAAAGUUAAUUUCAAUGUUUAAAGACUUGUUAUUAAAAUAAUAGCAGUUUCUAUAAAUUUAAUAUUUCAAUAAAACUCCCAGUAUUUAUUGUUAACACUGGAAAAAGUUUUCCAAAACGUAUAUGGCAGAAAUAUGGGCCUUGAUGUGAGGACAGCAUCAAUUAAUGAGGGAUCCUCUCCCUUGAUCAAAACACCUUCCACCAAGACCCACCUUUAACGCUGAGCAUUACCUCUCAAAGUGAGAUUUGGGCAGGGACUAAUAUCCAAACUGUAUCAACAUCUGACAAGGUGUUCACAACCAGAAUAUAUAAGGAGCUAUAACAAUUCUAUAGAAAAAAAAAUCUGAUUUAAAACUGGGCAAAAAUCUGAAUAGACGUUUCUCAAAAGAAGACAUACAAAUGGCAAACAGGCAUAUGAAAAGGUACUCAACAUCAUUGAUCCAUUAGAGAAAUGCAAAUCAAAACUACAAUAAGAUAUCAUCUCACCCCAGUUAAAAUGUCUUCUCUCCAAAAGACAGAUAAUAACAAAUGCUGAAGAGGAUGUGGAGAAAAGGGAAACCUCGUGCACUGUGGAAAUGUUAUUAGUACAACCACUAUGGACAACAAUUUGGAGGUACCUCAAAAACUAAAAAUAGAGCUAUCAUACAAUCCCACAAUUCCACUGGUAGUUAUAUACCCCAAAGACAGGAAAUCAGUAUAUUGAAGAUAUAUCUGCACCGUGUUUACUGUAGCACUACUCACAAUAGCCAAGAUUUGGAAGCAACCUAAGUGUCUAACAGCAGAUGAAUGGAUAAAUAAAAUAUGGUACAUAAACACAAUGGAGUACUAUUCAGCCAUAAAAAAGAAUGAGAUCCUGUCAUUUGCAACAUUGUAGAUGGAACUAGAGAUCAUUAAGUGAAAUAAGCCAGGCACAGCAAGACAGACAUCAUGUUCUGACGUAUUUGUUGGAGCUAAAGAUGAAAACAACUGAACUUAUAGAGGGUAGAAGGAUGUUUACCAGAGGCGGGAAAGGCAGUGAGGGCAUGGUGAGGGGGAAGUGGGGAAUGUUAACGGGCACAAAAUGUAGAAUGACUAAGACCUAGUAUUUGAUAGCACAAGGUUACUACAGUCAAUAAUAAUUGUGCAUUUUAAAGGUAUAAUUGAAUUGUAACACAAAGGAUAAAUGCUUGAGGUUAUGGAUACCCCAUUUACCCUGAUGUGAUUAUUAGACAUUGCAUGCCUAUAUCAAAAUAUAUCAUGUACCCCAUAGAUAUAUACACCUAGUAUGUACCCACAAAAAUUAAAAAUAAAGUAAAAUUUCAAUGAUUAGGAA